GUCCGGGUGACGUCUCCCGAGGGCGUCGGCAGGGUCGGCGGCGUCGGCAGCAGUGUCGACGGCAGCGGCGGCGGCGGGUGGGAAAUGGCGGAGUAUCUGGCCUCCAUCUUCGGCACCGAGAAAGACAAGGAGACGUGGGGUUUUAGCUUCCAGGGAACAGGAUCAACUCCUGAAAAAUGAAGCUGAUGAUGACUUCCUAAAGAUAUGCUAUUGUCUAAUCAAGUUAAAUAAUCUCAAGACCUAGUCAACUGUUCAUUUUAUUUCAAAAUUGGAGCAUGUCGUCAUGGAGACAGGUGCUCUCGGUUGCACAAUAAACCGACGUUUAGCCAGACCAUUGCCCUCUUGAACAUUUACCGUAACCCUCAAAACUCUUCCCAGUCUGCUGACGGUUUGCGCUGUGCCGUGAGCGAUGUGGAGAUGCAGGAACACUAUGAUGAGUUUUUUGAGGAGGUUUUUACAGAAAUGGAGGAGAAGUAUGGGGAAGUAGAGGAGAUGAACGUCUGUGACAACCUGGGAGACCACCUGGUGGGGAACGUGUACGUCAAGUUUCGCCGUGAGGAAGAUGCGGAAAAGGCUGUGAUUGACUUGAAUAACCGUUGGUUUAAUGGACAGCCGAUCCACGCCGAGCUGUCACCCGUGACGGACUUCAGAGAAGCCUGCUGCCGUCAGUAUGAGAUGGGAGAAUGCACACGAGGCGGCUUCUGCAACUUCAUGCAUUUGAAGCCCAUUUCCAGAGAGCUGCGGCGGGAGCUGUAUGGCCGCCGUCGCAAGAAGCAUAGAUCAAGAUCCCGAUCCCGGGAGCGUCGUUCUCGGUCUAGAGACCGUGGUCGUGGCGGUGGCGGUGGCGGUGGUGGAGGUGGCGGCGGACGGGAGCGUGACAGGAGGCGGUCGAGAGAUCGUGAAAGAUCUGGGCGAUUCUGAGCCAUGCCAUUUUUACCUUAUGUCUGCUAGAAAGUGUUGUAGUUGAUUGACCAAACCAGUUCAUAAGGGGAAUUUUUUUUAAAAAACAACAAAAAAAAAAACAUACAAAGAUGGGUUUCUGAAUAAAAUUUGUAGUGAUAACAGUA